AGUGGCUGGGAGCAGAUGGCAGUGCAGUCUAAAGCCUUCUGUGCGGGCGGCCUGGCCCCCGGCUGGAAGCUGCUGGUCCAGGGACAUGCUGACUCUGGAGAGGACAGGUUCGAGACUAACUUCUUGUUGGAGACGGGGGACAUUGCCUUCCACAUCAAGCCCCGGUUCUCCAGCGCCACUGUGGUGGGCAAUGCCUUCCAGUACGGCCGCUGGGGCCCGGAGCAGGUGUCUAGCAUCUUCCCGCUGGCCCCGGGGGAGCCCUUUGAGAUAGAGGUCAGCUGGGACGCGGAGCACUUCCACGUCUACGCCCCGGAGCACAAGGUGCUACAGUUCCCAUGCCGUCAGAGGCCGCUGGGCGCCACCACCAGGGUGCGCGUGCUGAGUGACCACUGCCUGGCCCAGGUGGAGCUGGCCAAGAGGGGCCUGAGCUGGGGGGACCGGGGCUACUGAGUGACACCUGCACCCCAGGAGCCAGCCUCGGCUUGUCCCAUGUCCAGGGUACCUGGAGUCCCACCCUGGGGCAGCUGGGUGAGGGGGUCUGUGGUCCUGUGUGCUCCUCGCAGCUCCACCUUCAAUAAACUCUGAGAAGGCU